AGACCUCCCGCACCAGGGCUCUGGUGAACAGCAAAUGCUCCACGCUGGGACGGGCCAUUGCCUGAUGCCUGUACAUGGUGGGCACUGAGAGACAAGAUUCCUGGGCCCUGCCUUCCAUACACUCCCCACGAUCUCGGAGGAAGCUCUGAGGACCCCGCUGAGAACCCACAGACAGGAGGACAACUGCGCUAUGACAGCAAUAAAGGCCAAGAAGGAGAAAGUUGAGGACCGCUGACAGCCCCGUGUGCUGUUGGGAGCUGCCCUUUCUACUUCAAACCUUCCUCUAGCAGACUGUGCAGGGACCCCCCACCACCACCAUCUGCCGCCAUGGUUGUGCAAAACAGCGCAGACGCCGGGGACAUGAGGGCAGGCGUGCAGCUGGAGCCCUUCCUGCACCAGGUCGGGGGGCACAUGAGCGUGAUGAAGUAUGACGAGCAUACGGUGUGCAAGCCCCUCGUCUCCCGGGAGCAGAGGUUCUAUGAAUCCCUGCCGCUGGCCAUGAAGCGGUUCACCCCACAGUACAAAGGUACCGUCACAGUGCACCUCUGGAAAGACAGCACAGGCCAUCUCAGCUUGGUUGCCAACCCAGUGAAGGAGAGCCAGGAGCCCUUCAAGGUCUCCACAGAGUCGGCGGCGGUGGCCAUAUGGCAGACGCUCCAGCAGACCACCGGCAGCAAUGGCAGCGACUGCACCCUUGCCCAGUGGCCGCAUGCCCAGCUGGCACGCUCACCCAAGGAGAGCCCGGCCAAGGCUCUUCUGAGGUCCGAGCCCCACCUCAACACUCCAGCCUUCUCGCUGGUGGAAGACACCAACGGAAACCAGGUUGAGAGGAAGAGCUUCAACCCGUGGGGCCUGCAAUGCCACCAGGCCCACCUGACCCGCCUGUGCUCCGAGUACCCAGAGAACAAGCGGCAUCGGUUCUUGUUGCUGGAAAAUGUAGUGUCACAGUACACGCAUCCCUGUGUCCUGGAUCUGAAGAUGGGGACCCGGCAGCACGGCGAUGAUGCAUCGGAGGAGAAGAAGGCCCGCCACAUGAGGAAGUGUGCGCAGAGCACCUCAGCCUGCCUGGGUGUGCGCAUCUGCGGCAUGCAGAUGUCCUUUGGAAAGCCGGGAAUGUAGUCCUCAAGAGAAUGGAGUGUGAUGAUUUGUGGUGUAAAUGGAAUCUCUCUCUGGACCUCAAAUCUUCUGAAAUUGAUCUGAUUUAUUUAGAAAGUGAUGCCUGUCAGGUAUUUUUGACGGCUGAUUUAGCAGCCAAUCUGCAGCCCUCCAAAGGCAACACUAAGGCUAUCAUAUCUUUCCGAUUUUUUUCAACACUGGUUUUCUAUGAACAUAUCAUGUAAUCUGAAGGCAGGAAAGACCUGAGAAACUGUCUUGGCCAGGCACAGGCUGCCCCUUCUAGGUAUGCCAGGCAGAGGGGUGCCACCCCCCCCCGGCCAUGCCCACUGCUGGCCUUAGUUCAGCCUCAGCUGCUGCCUGUGCCAUCUGAAUGAAAUGGGGGUUGCUGCCACUGUCCCCCAUCAGUAUCUCUCUUCCAUCUGCUCCCUUCUGGUGGCCAAGACACAACAGGGGAGGGGAGGAGAGAUGGUGCCAAGGAGAGGAGCCACCAGCCCCACAGAGCUGCCAUGAACCUCCCUCCUCCACCAGGCUCCCCUCAACUGCACUGGCUGCCUAGAAACCCUGUCCACACCUGACCUAGCCUGUCUUUUUAUCUUCAAACAAUUCACCCCACUCCACUUCAAGAGGCAUUACUGUUGCCUUGGAAUCUGCAGAGAAAGGACUUUAUAAACUUUGCUGAGGAAAUUUUAAUCUAGUUGGCUUUCCAAGGCCAUUGGCUGUGAUUUCAGAUUCCUAUUAAAGCUUUCUAGCUUGGGUUUGCUAAUAUUUGAAUUGAAGAGGGCCAGGAGCCAGGGCUUAAAUCAUGAUUUGGAGGUUGACAUUGGAAAUUCACAAGAAAGAAGAUCCAAACGUUUUCCUCGUGGGUGGAGGGUCACCUCUGUGGGGUGAAGGAUCUUUAGACCUUGGAUUACUAUUAAAGACUUGCACAGAAAGCAUUUUAAAAUGUAAAAGCUACUCUGGCACUUGAUGGAAGAUCAUCUUCUGCUCAUUUCAGUCACUCUUGCCCUACAUCUCCUAAAAAUCUGUUCAUAUAUUAUCCCAGCUUAUGAUGCUGCAACCGUACCAGAUACAAUUUGUUUAAGUUUCCAAUCUUCACAUUUUCUUUAUUCUUUUUAAUGUAAGGUUUAUCAAACAGAUAAGAAGUACUUUCUCUGCAAAGACAAGUACUAUGGAAGAAAACUCUCAGUGGAGGGGUUCAGACAAGCCCUCUAUCAGUUCCUACAUAAUGGAAGCCACCUCCGGAGGGAGCUCCUGGAGCCCAUCCUGCACCAGCUCCGGGCCCUCCUCUCUGUCAUUAGGAGCCAGAGUUCAUACCGCUUCUAUUCCAGCUCUCUCCUUGUCAUCUAUGAUGGGCAGGAACCACCAGAAAGAGCCCCAGGCAGCCCGCAUCCUCACGAGGCUCCCCAGGCAGCCCACGGUAGCUCUCCCGGUGGUCUCACCAAGGUUGACAUCCGCAUGAUUGACUUUGCUCAUACCACAUACAAGGGCUACUGGAAUGAGCACACCACCUACGAUGGACCAGACCCUGGCUAUAUUUUUGGCCUGGAAAACCUCAUCAGGAUCCUGCAGGAUAUCCAAGAGGGAGAAUGAAACUUCCUGGGCUUAUCUGGAUUCUUCUGGGCUAUAGAUCUCAAAUAGAGACCUGUUGGUUGCUAGGGUAGUCCAGACACCCCUUAGAUGUCUUCAUAAUAGUCCUAUCUACCUUCAAAAACCAUCUCUAUAUAUGGCAGACUAUAUUAACAGCUGCUGAACAAAUCAGCUCUGGAGGUGAUUCCACAUCCCCUGGCAUUAUGCUCUAAUGCUGCUCAUCGGAGAACAGACAGCCAGGAUAAAGUGGCACCUUCUGGAGUACACUGGAGGGGGCAGCCCAAGUUAGAGGCCAGCAUUGCUGACAUUCUGGAAUAUUUGCAUCUAAAAAUGUUUACUCGUUGCCAUGCUGCAGUCCGCACAAGCUGUGAGGCAGAAAACUUGACUUGAAGCAGCCUUGAAGAGUGAGUUCAUGAGCUCAUGGUUUUUCUCCUUGUAUGGACUGCUCGCUCCAAGGGCAGGCAGAGCUCAUGAAUGCCUCUUAUCUUCCUAAGCGGAGUUUUAGGUGACACAGGAUGAAGCAGAAGAGAUCUACCCAUCUCAUCUGCUCUGCACCCAGCUUCUAAGUGGACAAAGCCAAGCCCAGGCAUGAGCUCUGGCAAAGCAAGACCCCAGAUUCUCCAUUUUUGCCUGUGGAAAGGAGGGUCCCUUUACAGGCUUUUUUUUCCUUUUUUUCCCCCAAAAUCUCUUAAAAUGAGGAAUCUCUUAGCAGACUUUGGAGUUCCCCAUUCUGCCACAUUCUGACCAUGAGACGCGGCUUGCAGUGGGGGUGAACGCACAUAAAAAGGGACCACUGACGUCCUGCUCUACUCUCUGCUUUCUAUUUAUUUAUUUUGGGGGUGGGUUGGGGAGUCAGAAGAACCUGGAGGACGGAGGAAACCAGGGGCAAUGUUUACAAGACUGGUGGACAAGUGUAAAUAUGGAAUAAGAACAAACAGUUCUAAUUAAUUCCUUCUUCUGCAGUAUGGAAACCUAUUACGAUGCCCUUGAGUCAAGCACUGAGAUACGUUACCCAAUUAGGGAAAUAAAUUUGUUAAUAAAAUUGCUGAGGUCACCAGUGA